UUUAUUUGCAUGUUUCAUAAUUUUUUGUUAAAUACUGAACAUUUUAGAUAAUAUAUUGUAGUAAUUCUAGAUUAUGUUUUCCUCUUGAAGAUUGUUAUUGCUUUGUUUGUUAAUCCCUGAAUGAAAUCUGUGAAAUCUGUCUUCCCUACAACAUGUGGCCUCUGAUGUUUCCAUUCAGUUUUAUUUCCUUCUUAUUUUUAUUUUAAGCCUUGUUUCUUAGGGGUUUCCCCCAUAUCUGCAUAGCUUAGUGUUCAGCCAGAGAUUUUUCGGAGGUUGUGCUCAAGAACCUCAAGCUAGUUAGACUUUGUGUCUGCCUAUAGUUCUAUGUGUGAGCUGGGGAGGGCAAAGUUCAGGUUGUUUUCAAACCUACCCUGGCUUUUACUCUUCACCAGACUCUUUUAUUUCCCCUGCACACAUAUAUAAGCUCCAUUGGCUAGGGAUGUGUGGGUGGCUCAGGCUUCUCUGGUCUCUGCUGUGCAUUCACCCAGCUUCGAGUUAACCCAAGAUAUGUGGAGAGCUUAUCAAACUCCCUUGGUCUGUCUCACUCCCUGGAAUUUUCUGAUAAAUUCCUGGUUAGUUUGCCAGUCCAUUGUUUGGCCCAAACAUUGCUGAAACCCAGCCUAACAGUGCUUCUGGCCUUUCCUGUUCUUGAUAUUAUAACUGACAAUGCCCCAAAUUAAGUGGAGCCCUCUGGCAGAGGCAGUGAAGCAGCUGAUUUUUCACAGGCGGCACCACGUUUGUUGAAGUAUUGCAACUGAUAGCAUUGGGAGCCUGGUGAACGAGAGCAGCCUCAGGCAAGAAUACUAUAGAGUCGUGCUAUUCUUACCCAAAGUCCAGUAAUUUUUAUGAAUACAUGUUUCUUUGUUGUAUGUCUUUGAUUGAUUUGCAGAGUGAUAAAAUGGUGGGUUUUGACAGUUUGUCCUGCUUUAGAGUCGUAUUUUCUUCUGUUCUCAGUUUUAUCUUUUAAGCUUGGAACUUUUAAACAUCAUUUAAAAGUUAUUUUAUUUUAGCUAAGGUAGCACUGGCUGCUUUAACAGAGAAAUCUUGAAUUCUCAAUGGCUUAACUCAAUAAAAGUUAGUUUUUGUUUAUGUCACAAUUUGUAUUUUCUAUUGCUAUGUAAGUUAUCCCCAAAUGUAGUAUCUUUAAACAACAAAUAUUUAUUAUCUCACAGUUUCUGUGGAUCAGGAAUCUGAGUGCAGCCUGGCUGGGUGCGACUGGGUCAAGUGUCUCACAAAGUUGCAAUCAAGGUGUUGGCCAAGGCUGCAGCAUCUCAAGGCUUCACUGGGUGAAGAUCUGCUUCCAUGCUCACUCACAUGGCUGUUGGCAGGCUACAGAUCCUUGCUGGCUACUAACCAGGGACAUCAAUUUCUUCUAUGUGAGACUCACUACAGGGCUACUCACAGCAUAGCAGCUUGCCUCCCCCAGAGCAAAGGCUUUGAGAGAAAGAGAAUAAGAAAAGGUGUCUAAGAUGGAAGCCACAGUCUGUUUGUAACCUAAUCUCAGAAGUGAUAUCCCAUUGUAUCUGCCAUAUUCUAUUCAUUAGAAGUGGGCCAAUAAGUCUGGUCCACACUCAUGAGAAAGGGAUUACACAAGGGUGUGAGUUCCAGGAGAUGGAGAUCAUUAGGAGCUAUUUCAGAGGCUGUCUCCCACAUAAUACACUCACCUUCAAUGGAAAUUUAUCUGUGAGAAGCAUGAGCAGCUUGGGUUAGGAGUGAGUUCCCCAGGAAAUAUUUUGCAGUUGCUUCUGUUGGAAUAUGCCUGGUUUGGAACUAUUUUAUGCUAAUUUUUAAUUUUAGGGGUGUGGCCCAUGAAGGUUCAUGCAGAUACACUGUACCGUGGCUGUGUGAGGACCAGCUUGUAGGUACAGAUUCUUAGGGGAUUUGCCUCUUUUCCCUUCCCGCCAUCCCUGUACUUCAGACCAGCUUCCUUGUCAUCAGCCUGUGGUGAUGACUAAUUUUUUUAUUCUAGUCUACAUUUUCAUCAAAGGUUUCACUUUUCCUAACUUUAUGCAGGUUCUCCUUUCCAAUUCCACGCUUCAUGUGGGCCCAAAGCCUUCCUCCUAUGCCCAAGUGGGUGUUAAAACCUAAGCCUUUACCAAAACGCUGAGACCAACAGCCCCUGCCCCCACCUCCCGCCUCCACUGGGCUGUUUGCAGCAUUGGCUCACACAGUUAAUAUUCUGAUUUUCCAGUCUCCUCUUUGCUUUUGUCCCCUGGGGACUUAUCUCGCUUUCUUGUGAGCUCAGCUAUGCAUAUAAAGCAACAUUUGUUAUAUUUCAUCCAAUGUUUUGAAAUGGGAGAGUUUUCUAAAGGUUAUCUAAACUAAAUAACACAAGUAAAGUAUACACGAUGUUGCCUGGCCCCCUGUUGGACCCACCAACUCUAGUCUGGACAAUUUCCAAUUAGACACAAAGCAUUUUUACUUUAAAUAUUUCAUGAGCUUGGAAAUGGCUACUGAUUCCAGUCUGGUUUGGAGAAAGGCUAAGGAUCUCAUCCCAAGAGGAUUCUUUGACUUUGAGUCUCCUGUAAAUGGAUGUUGGGGGAAGCAGGGUGGAAGUCAGUGCAGGGAUAAUAGGAGCAUUCACAGUACAAUGUUACAGUUUUAUAACUGUAGGAUAGUAAAGAUCAACAUGGGUGUAAUAUUUCUCUGAGAGUCUCUGAGUCCGUGUUUCCCUUGUGUCCUGGUCUCCUGUUGGAACCCCAGAAGCUCCUCUUGGCCAGCUGAGCUGGCGGGUGUAUGACCCCAGGGAGUUGUUCACCUUCUUUUGUCUGCCUUGGAUAGAAUUGGUUCUCAGCGAUGAGUUGAACCAGCAGCUGGAGGCCGUGUGCGGGUCGGUGUUUGGGGAGCUGGAGUCCCAGGCCGUGGACGCCCUGGACCUGCCCGGCUGUUUCCGCAUGCGGAGCCACAGCUACCUCCGGGCCAUCCAGGCCGGCUGCUCUCAAGACGACGACUGCCUGCCCCUCCUCGCUACCCCUGCCGCUGUCUCAGGGAGGCCCGGCUCCUCCUUCAACUUCAGAAAGGCCCCGCCCCCCAUCCCGCCGGGAAGCCAGGCCCCGCCCCGCAUCUCCAUCACCGCCCAGAGCAGCACCGACUCCGCGCACGAGAGCUUCACGGCGGCCGAGGGCCCCGCCCGGCGCUGCAGCUCCGCCGACGGGCUGGACGGCCCCGCCAUGGGUGCGCGCACACUGGAGUUGGCGCCGGUGCCGCCCCGGGCCAGCCCCAAGCCCCCCACACUCAUCAUCAAGACCAUCCCUGGCAGGGAGGAGCUGCGGAGCCUGGCGCGGCAGCGGAAGUGGCGGCCGUCCAUUGGGGUGCAGGUGGAGACGAUCUCAGAUUCGGACACCGAGAACAGGAGCCGGAGGGAGUUCCACUCUAUUGGCGUGCAGGUGGAAGAGGACAAGAGGCGAGCAAGGUUCAAGCGCUCCAAUAGUGUGACGGCUGGCGUGCAGGCAGACCUGGAGCUGGAGGGCCUGGCAGGCCUGGCCACGGUGGCCACAGAAGACAAGGCCCUGCAGUUUGGACGCUCCUUCCAGAGGCACGCCUCUGAGCCCCAGCCUGGGCCCCGGGCCCCCACCUACUCAGUCUUCCGCACGGUCCACACGCAGGGCCAGUGGGCCUACCGCGAGGGCUACCCACUGCCGUACGAGCCGCCGGCCACCGAUGGGUCGCCCGGCCCUGCCCCCGCCCCCACCCCCGGCCCUGGGGCCGGCCGCCGUGACUCCUGGAUAGAGCGCGGUUCACGUAGCCUCCCCGACUCAGGCCGCGCAUCCCCCUGCCCACGCGACGGCGAGUGGUUCAUCAAGAUGCUGCGGGCAGAGGUGGAGAAGCUGGAGCACUGGUGCCAGCAGAUGGAGCGUGAGGCGGAGGACUAUGAGCUACCCGAGGAGAUCCUGGAGAAGAUCCGCAGUGCUGUGGGCAGCACACAACUUCUCCUGUCCCAGAAGGUUCAGCAGUUCUUCCGGCUGUGUCAGCAAAGCAUGGAUCCCACUGCGUUCCCUGUGCCCACCUUCCAGGACCUGGCGGGUUUCUGGGACCUCCUACAGCUCUCCAUCGAGGAUGUGACCCUCAAGUUCCUGGAGCUACAGCAACUCAAGGCCAACAGCUGGAAACUCCUGGAGCCUAAGGAGGAGAAGAAGGUCCCUCCGCCGAUACCAAAGAAGCCCCUGCGGGGCCGGGGCGUGCCGGUGAAGGAGCGCUCCCUGGACUCCGUGGACCGGCAGCGGCAGGAAGCGCGCAAGCGGCUCCUGGCGGCCAAGCGCGCCGCUUCCUUCCGCCACAGCUCGGCCACCGAGAGCGCCGACAGCAUCGAGAUCUACAUCCCCGAGGCCCAGACCAGGCUGUGACCGGUCCGGCCCGCCCAGCCCGGCCCGGGCCCGCGGUUCUCCACCCGUACUGUACACCCAGCGUCGAGGUCACUGUGAACGCGGGCCGCCCCGUGCGCCCGCCCCACCGGCACCGGACGCCCCGGCCCCCGGGCCCGUCACACUCUCGUGGGUUUUUUACCUUCCUGAUCCCACGCGAAGGCGCCCGGGCUGGGCAGGGGGCCGUGCCUCUCCGCCCUGCGCCCCUCACCUGGAUCCCCUGCCCACCUGGUCCGACGCUUUGUCCCCACCUCCUCCCCAUGGGCACCAUCUCUGCCAUUCUUUCCCCCACGGGCCAGGCCGGGCCGGGUCCCUCAUCUGGGCUCUGCGUCCCCCCCUCCCCCACCCCGCGGGGCUGGGCUUCGUGGGGAUCAAGCUUCGUGGCUUUUUAUGAAGAAUCCCGAACCCUGCCUAGGAGCCCGCCCCACCCUCCCAGGGGCUCCAUCCUCAGCCCUCUGCCCACUGGGCCCAGGGACCACAGUGGCUGGACCAACCCAGGACCAGGGCGCCUGGGCCUCUCCCCUUUCCCAGCGGCUGGGGAGGGGAGAUGGGGGCUUCCCCUCACCACACCUGUGGCUGUUCCCACAUCCCCUUGAAUAUCCCAGGAAAAAUAAAACGGCAGAACUGCA